CUUUCCUACGCAGCCGCUCCUGCCGCCGUGGUCGCUGGAGCUUUGCCUCUCUAGGCCGGCAGCGCCUCUCCUCCAUGGUCCUGUCUGUCAGCGCUGUUUUGGGAGCCCGCCGGUGAGGCCGGGCCACGCUCAGACACUUCGAUCGUCGAGUCUGUCACUGGGCAUGGCGGGUCAGUUCCGCAGCUACGUGUGGGACCCGCUGCUGAUCCUGUCGCAGAUCGUCCUCAUGCAGACCGUGUAUUACGGCUCGCUGGGCCUGUGGCUGGCGCUGGUGGACGGGCUAGUGCGAAGCAGCCCCUCGCUGGACCAGAUGUUCGACGCCGAGAUCCUGGGCUUUUCCACCCCUCCAGGCCGGCUCUCCAUGAUGUCCUUCAUCCUCAACGCCCUCACCUGACAGGGUCUUGCUCUCUUGCCCAGGCUGGAGUGCAGUGGCGAAGUCACAGCUCACUGCAGCCUCGACUCCUGGGCUUAAGCGAUCCUCCGACCUCAGCCUCCUGAGUAGCUGAUACUACAAGCGCAAGGCACCACAUCUGGCUAAUUUUUAAAUUUUUUGUAGAGACAGUGUCUCAUUAUGUUGCCCAGGAUGGUCUUGAACUCCUGGCCUCAAGCAGUCUUCCUGCCUCGACCUCCCAAGGUGCUGGGAUUACAGGCGUGAGCCACCAUGCCUAGCCUGUUCAGAGUAAAUCUUAUUUGAGGCAUGAAUCAAUCAAACAUAAAUAGAGAGUUGAAUUGAUCUUAGAGGGAAUGGGAUGCAGCAAAGCCCUACUUGACCAUCUCCCCCCUCCCACAUUUGGAAAUCCUUAAACCCACUUAUGUAGGCCUCUGACUGUGAGAUUCAGAGCCACAGCAGUUUCCACCUCUGCUAAGGCCUUCAGGCAGUGAGAUGGCUCACUUCAGUGCCCCUCCUUCCACACAUCUCCUAGCUGUAUCCUGAGACGCCUCAACCUAGUCACUACCCUUCUGUAUGAUGUUGGUCUAAGGCUUCCCCCUCUCUGGACAUGAAGGCGGAGCCUCCCAGCACUACCAGCCACACACCACUCAAGACUCCAGAUCCUGAACCCUGACUCUGGGGCCCAGCUCUGGGCCUGGCUUGGGGCUUGCAUCUCACCUAGCCUGGCAGUGUUGUUGUCACACCCACCUUGUAUGGAUGCCACAUAGGCAUUUCAAGUGAUGCGGAGCAGAAGCGGGUGCAGCGGCGCUUGACCCAACGCAGGGUGGAGGAUCUGCACAUCACCCUGGGCGCCGGGAGGUGGAUUCGUGUGGGCAGCCCCUCAAACCAGAUCCACUGGUCGGCUACAUCCAGCUGCUUCAUGUGCCCCAUGGGAGUUCUAUUGCGGUAGGGCUUAAUGAAGAUGACUCGGGGGCCCUCGGUGAGUGGUUGCCUCCCCUGGACUCCAGGGUUCAAGCUAUCAUCCCUCGAUGUCCUUGGAACCUCAGGCUCUAUAUGCUUUUCUUUCCGUGGCAUUGCCGCCAAUGACGUUUUCUCCUUGUUCCUCAUCCCUGACUGCACCUGGGACUUCCACUCCUUGUACUCUUUUUUCUUAGGGUCCCCUGUGGACUCUAAUUUCUUGGACUUGAGUUCCUUCUCGGAGCACCCGAUCUCCUGGAACUCUUCAUUAUUUUGUUUUGUUUUAUUGCAGGCACUGUUUUCCCUGGCAGGGAGAGGAAAGGCAGUCAGCACAGCAGGACCGAGGCCCUGGUUCCCGAGACAGUUGCUAUGUAGCCAGCUCAGGGGAGCCUGUUAAGAAAGGCUAGAGGGGCCUGCAAAGAAACUUCUCUACUGCCCAGAGGCCUUGUGCUGGUGUGAGGAGGUGUGAUGAGCACUAGCAGAGGGAUGUGAGAGAUUGGGAAGGUGAAAGCCAUGACUAGUAGUUAAGGCCCCUAAGAAUGAAUAUUGUCUACAUCAUCUGCCACUAGAUUAGGGUUCUGUCUCUCUGGACUUCAGCUGGGAGGGUGAACAGUCCAGUAGUUUUUCUAAAUUGUGCUCCAAGAACCUUAGGGUUCUGAGGAGGUGUCUCAAUGUCACCUCCCCUGACCCACUGGGGCAGGAUACCUCUCCCCAGCUCAUAACAACACAAUUGGGGCUUGGAAAUAGAUAUUUGAACAGAGGUUUCACUGCUUUAAUAAAGUUGGAAAACUGUUCAAGACCAGCCUGGGCAACAUGGUGAGACUCUGUCUCCAUACAAAAAAAAAAUUUUUAAGUUGGAAAAUGAUGGGGCUAGAUGAUCCUGAUCCUUCUAGCUCUAUGUUUCCUGAUUGCCUGCGACUAGAGGCCAAAUCAGAAAGAGGAGCCCAGAAAGGUGGCCUUGACAGAAAUAUUAAAUGCUGAGACUUUCCCAAAGGGUGUCUGUAACAGACUGGGCCCCCUGCAAACCCCCAGUGGCAACACCAUCCUAGCCAAGGGCGUGGAGAGAGAUGAGGCCUUGGGCUGCAGAUAAUGGCAAUACUGUGAUGAUAAUAAUGGCUCCCGCUGAUUGAGUCCUCGCUCUAUGCCAGACUCGGGACCCUUACAACUUGGGAUCCUUACUAUUUCUGUGAAGUAGAAGGCAGUGAAACAGAGUGGCUUACAGAGCACAGGUGUUGGAUUCAGACAAACGGGCUCAGAUUCUGCUUCUGCCUCUUACCACCUGUGUGAUUUGGGCAAGAUAUUUAACCUCUCAGAGCCUUAGCUUCCUUAUCUGUAAAACUAGGAUAAUUCUGUCUACCUAACAGGAUUGUUGUGAAGAAUAAACUAAAUGGGAAAAUUCUUAAGUGCUUAACACUGUAGGAUGGUACUUAGCAGGCACCAAUCAAUGUUAGCUUUCUUAAUACUGUCAUGUGACUUAUGAGGAAACGGUUUGAACUUGUCUCGGAGGCAUGGUAAAAAAAAAUAAAAAUAAAAAUAAAUUAAUAAAGAAA